AAACACUCUGUGUGGCUCCUCGGCUUUGACAGAGUGCAAGACGAUGACUUGCAAAAUGUCGCAGCUGGAACGCAACAUAGAGACCAUCAUCAACACCUUCCACCAAUACUCUGUGAAGCUGGGGCACCCAGACACCCUGAACCAGGGGGAAUUCAAAGAGCUGGUGCGAAAAGAUCUGCAAAAUUUUCUCAAGAAGGAGAAUAAGAAUGAAAAGGUCAUAGAACACAUCAUGGAGGACCUGGACACAAAUGCAGACAAGCAGCUGAGCUUCGAGGAGUUCAUCAUGCUGAUGGCGAGGCUAACCUGGGCCUCCCACGAGAAGAUGCACGAGGGUGACGAGGGCCCUGGCCACCACCAUAAGCCAGGCCUCGGGGAGGGCACCCCCUAAGACCACAGUGGCCAAGAUCACAGUGGCCACGGCCACGGCCACAGUCAUGGUGGCCACGGCCACAGCCACUAAUCAGGAGGCCAGGCCACCCUGCCUCUACCCAACCAGGGCCCCGGGGCCUGUUAUGUCAAACUGUCUUGGCUGUGGGGCUAGGGGCUGGGGCCAAAUAAAGUCUCUUCCUCCAA